CUGCACCAUAGCAGUGAUGGGGCCAGGGGUGGGUGUGGUAGGAGAUGCUGAGGCAAAUAGGUCUUUGUCCUAAUCUCCAACUCUGGAAAGCCAUUCUAUCCAUCCUUGUCUCCACGGAGGGCCCUGCCUUGCAGCCUCCUUCCUGUCCCCGGCGUCCGCUUCGGGCCUUUCCUUACCCCACCCCCCUGCUAAGGGAAGUCUCAGUCAACCCUAUUGCUCUGCCCAUCCCCUGCCUUUCGUUGAGUUCUUCCAGCUGUCUAAUGUGCUACAGCGUUCUGUCCCUACAAGAGGAGCAGUACCCCGCUCCCCACAGACUUAGCCUAACUGGUGUGUGUGCCUUUCCUGGGUGGAGGGGGCUUCCUGAUUCUUCUGGAAGCCAGAAGAGACUGGACUGGGGUUGGGGGCUGGGGGAUUUGGCACCAGUACCUCAGGUUCUGUGAAGCUCUCCAGAGCCUAUGUGUCCAAAGGGAGGAUACGAACUUAUCUGCCCCUUCCUCCUCUCCAUUCAAGAGGCAGGGGGCUGGACCAGAUGACUUUUGAGGGUGAAAGCCCAGGCCUUCUGCAUCUAGAGGGCUACUUAAGCACAGGCCUGCAUGUAUGUGCAUAUACAAGCCCAUGCCCAGGUCACCAGGCAGCAUGCGGGGCCCCAAGUGGGCCUCCACAUGUGGGCACAGGCUGGUGACAGAUUCCUCUCUCCCCAGGAUGCCUCCCCAGCUGCCCAGCCAGGCCCAUCAUGGGAGGGCCCCAGGCUCCCCCAACAACACGCCCGCACACACGUGCAGCAGGGCACGCACAUGCUGAUCUCAGGGUCCCCACGGUGCAAGAGGCUGGGAAUGGGGGUUUUGAGCACUGAGUCCAGGCCGCUGCCAAAAUCCAUCGGAAUCUUGUCCCCUCCAGGACCCCAUCUCCGGCUGUGGAGGUCACAACAGCAGAUGGCUGCUCCUGUCCCGUGGGCCUGCUGUGCUGUGCUUGCCGCCGCCGCCGCAGUUGUCUACGCCCAGAGACACAGUCCACAGGAGGCACCCCAUGUGCAGUACGAGCGCCUGGGCUCUGACGUGACACUGCCAUGUGGGACAGCAAACUGGGAUGCUGCGGUGACGUGGCGGGUAAAUGGGACAGACCUGGCCCCUGACCUGCUCAACGGCUCUCAGCUGGUGCUCCAUGGCCUGGAACUGGGCCACAGUGGCCUCUACGCCUGCUUCCACCGUGACUCCUGGCACCUGCGCCACCAAGUCCUGCUGCAUGUGGGCUUGCCGCCGCGGGAGCCUGUGCUCAGCUGCCGCUCCAACACUUACCCCAAGGGCUUCUACUGCAGCUGGCAUCUGCCCACCCCCACCUACAUUCCCAACACCUUCAAUGUGACUGUGCUGCAUGGCUCCAAAAUUAUGGUCUGUGAGAAGGACCCAGCCCUCAAGAACCGCUGCCACAUUCGCUACAUGCACCUGUUCUCCACCAUCAAGUACAAGGUCUCCAUAAGUGUCAGCAAUGCCCUGGGCCACAAUGCCACAGCUAUCACCUUUGACGAGUUCACCAUUGUGAAGCCUGAUCCUCCAGAAAAUGUGGUAGCCCGGCCAGUGCCCAGCAACCCUCGCCGGCUGGAGGUGACGUGGCAGACCCCCUCGACCUGGCCUGACCCUGAGUCUUUUCCUCUCAAGUUCUUUCUGCGCUACCGACCCCUCAUCCUGGACCAGUGGCAGCAUGUGGAGCUGUCCGACGGCACAGCACACACCAUCACAGAUGCCUACGCCGGGAAGGAGUACAUUAUCCAGGUGGCAGCCAAGGACAAUGAGAUUGGGACAUGGAGUGACUGGAGCGUAGCCGCCCACGCUACGCCCUGGACUGAGGAACCGCGACACCUCACCACGGAGGCCCAGGCUGCGGAGACCACGACCAGCACCACCAGCUCCCUGGCACCCCCACCUACCACGAAGAUCUGUGACCCUGGGGAGCUGGGCAGCGGCGGGGGACCCUCGGCACCCUUCUUGGUCAGCGUCCCCAUCACUCUGGCCCUGGCUGCCGCUGCCGCCACUGCCAGCAGUCUCUUGAUCUGAGCCCGGCACCCCAUGAGGACAUGCAGAGCACCUGCAGAGGAGCAGGAGGCCGGAGCUGAGCCUGCAGACCCCGGUUUCUAUUUUGCACACGGGCAGGAGGACCUUUUGCAUUCUCUUCAGACACAAUUUGUGGAGACCCCGGCGGGCCCGGGCCUGCCGCCCCCCAGCCCUGCCGCACCAAGCUGGCCCUCCUUCCUCCCUCAGGGGAGGUGGGCCAUGCAGCUAACCCACCCACCAAAGACCCCCUCACCCUGGCCCCUUGGGCUGGACCCUCCAAUGCCAGCGACUCCCAGGAGCCCUUGGGGGACGUGAGGGGAGCCUCUCACAUCCGAUUUCUCCUCCUGCCCCAGCCUCCUGUCUAUCCCAGGGUCUCUGUUGCCACCAUCAGAUUAUAAGCUCCUGAUGCUGGGGGGGCCCAGCCAUCCCCCUCCCCCCAGCACCCACAAUUUUCAGUCCCCUCCCCUCUGCCCUGUUUUGUAUACCCCUCCCCUGACCCUGCUCCUAUCCCACAGUAUUUAAUGCCCUGUCAGUCCCUUCUAGUCUGACUCAAUGGUAACUUGCUGUAUUUGAAUUUUUUAUAGAUGUAUAUACAGGGUGGGGGGAGUGGGCGGUUCUCAUUAAACGUCACCAUUUCAUGA